GGAAGCGGAAGAGGCGCUCGGAGCGGGGAGUGGGGCCUAGCUGCAGCCGGAGCCUGGGAGACGAUGCAUCACUGUAAGCGAUACCGCUCCCCUGAACCAGACCCGUACCUGAGCUACCGAUGGAAGAGGAGGAGGUCCUACAGUCGGGAACAUGAAGGGAGACUGCGAUACCCGUCCCGAAGGGAGCCUCCCCCACGAAGAUCUCGGUCCAGAAGCCAUGACCGCCUGCCCUACCAGAGGAGGUACCGGGAGCGCCGUGACAGCGAUACAUACCGGUGUGAAGAGCGGAGCCCAUCCUUUGGAGAGGACUACUAUGGACCUUCACGUUCUCGUCAUCGUCGGCGAUCGCGGGAGAGGGGGCCAUACCGGACCCGCAAGCAUGCCCACCACUGCCACAAACGCCGCACCAGGUCUUGUAGCAGCGCCUCCUCGAGAAGCCAACAGAGCAGUAAGCGCAGCAGCCGGAGUGUGGAAGAUGACAAGGAGGGUCACCUGGUGUGCCGGAUCGGCGAUUGGCUCCAAGAGCGAUAUGAGAUUGUGGGGAACCUGGGUGAAGGCACCUUUGGCAAGGUGGUGGAGUGCUUGGACCAUGCCAGAGGGAAGUCUCAGGUUGCCCUGAAGAUCAUCCGCAACGUGGGCAAGUACCGGGAGGCUGCCCGGCUAGAAAUCAACGUGCUCAAAAAAAUCAAGGAGAAGGACAAAGAAAACAAGUUCCUGUGUGUCUUGAUGUCUGACUGGUUCAACUUCCACGGUCACAUGUGCAUCGCCUUUGAGCUCCUGGGCAAGAACACCUUUGAGUUCCUGAAGGAGAAUAACUUCCAGCCUUACCCCCUACCACAUGUCCGGCACAUGGCCUACCAGCUCUGCCACGCCCUUAGAUUUCUGCAUGAGAAUCAGCUGACCCAUACAGACUUGAAACCAGAGAACAUCCUGUUUGUGAAUUCUGAGUUUGAAACCCUCUACAAUGAGCACAAGAGCUGUGAGGAGAAGUCAGUGAAGAACACCAGCAUCCGAGUGGCUGACUUUGGCAGUGCCACAUUUGACCAUGAGCACCACACCACCAUUGUGGCCACCCGUCACUAUCGCCCGCCUGAGGUGAUCCUUGAGCUGGGCUGGGCACAGCCCUGUGACGUCUGGAGCAUUGGCUGCAUUCUCUUUGAGUACUACCGGGGCUUCACACUCUUCCAGACCCACGAAAACCGAGAGCACCUGGUGAUGAUGGAGAAGAUCCUAGGGCCCAUCCCAUCACACAUGAUCCACCGUACCAGGAAGCAGAAAUAUUUCUACAAAGGGGGCCUAGUUUGGGAUGAGAACAGCUCUGACGGCCGGUAUGUGAAGGAGAACUGCAAACCUCUGAAGAGUUACAUGCUCCAAGACUCCCUGGAGCACGUGCAGCUGUUUGACCUGAUGAGGAGGAUGUUAGAAUUUGACCCUGCCCAGCGCAUCACACUGGCCGAGGCCCUGCUGCACCCCUUCUUUGCUGGCCUGACCCCUGAGGAGCGGUCCUUCCACACCAGCCGCAACCCAAGCAGAUGACAGGCACAGGCCACCGCAUGAGGAGAUGGAGGGCGGGACUGGGCCGCCCAGCCCCUUGACUCCAGCCUCGACCGCCAGGCCCCAGGCCAGAGCCACCCAAUGAACAGUGCAAUGUGAAGGAAGGCAGGAGCCUGCAGGGGAGCAGACUUGGUGCCCAGCUGCCAGAAAGCACAGAUUUGACCCAAGCUAUUUAUAUGUUAUAAAGUUAUAAUAAAGUGUUUCUUACUGUUUGUAACCCCUGGUACCAGUGUGUCCAUCUCCAGGCUCCUUGCCUUCCCCUUACCUGACCUUAUUAAUAAAGUCUUUCUUAGCAGUUCA